UAAUAUUUAAAAUGCUGUUCUAGGCUCCAAAGUUACAACAUAAAUAAAACAGUCAAUGUCCUCAAAAAUCUCACAAUCUAAUGAGAAAACAGAAAUUUGAGAAUUCAUUCAUUAUAGUACAAGGUAAAGUAAAGGAAAUACUUUGAUGUCAAUAUGAAAUUAUCUAUGGGAGUACAGAGGAUUUAAAGAUGAAACUUUAUAAAGUGAGAAAGAUUUCACUUUUGUCUUAGAUGAUUAGAAGAAUUUCACAUGUUUUAAUAGAGAUAUUAAUCAAAAGCCAAAAUAUGGACAAGAACUCUGGAGAUAGCUAAAGAAAUUUACAAUUUUGGGAAAUGGAGAACAGAGCUGUAUGACUGAGGUAUGGUGAGGAGUGAUGAUCGAUAAGCCAAGAAGUGAAGACGCAGGUUAGAAUUUGAAGAACCCCCUUUCUUUUCCAUGUUAAGUUGUCAGGUAGUGAGGUACUACUGAACAGUUUGACCUUUGGAAUGGGUUGAGUUAAACCUGAGUGUCUAUGUUUUAGAAAGUUAUCAUUUGUGACAACACACCGUUGUAAAAUCUGUAGUUUUCCUAAUAUAUGUGAAGAUACUCUUGGCUGUGACAAUGUAUUAAAAGGAAGGGAAAGAUACAUUAAAAGUUAGAAUUAGGACUUAGUGUUUGAAUGAAAAUGGAAGUUUAGGAGGCAUCAGGAUUAAAGACGGCAUCAAGAUUUCUACUUAGUACAUUGCAUACAUGUGUAAUCAAGUGUGAAUUAUUAAACAAAACUAGAUACUUCAUAUCUCGUUAUGUAACUACUACUUAAUAUUUUUAACCUAAGUGUUCUUAAUUCUGCAAAGAAUUCUAAAUUUAAAAUGCCUAAGUAAUCUUUUUCAGUUCAUGCAAAUAUAUAUGUGUGGGCAUGUUUGUGUGGGUGUCUUGUUUUACUAAAAUAUCUUCAAGAAUAAUGUUUGAGGGAAAAAAAUAUUAAGAACAUAAAAAUGGGCCAGGUGCGGUGGCUCAUGCCCAUAAUCCCAGCACUUUGGGAGGCCAAGGUGGGUGGAUCACCUGAGGUCAGGAGUUCAAGACCAGCCUGGCCAACAUGAUGAAACCCCAUCUCUACUAAAAAUACAAAAACUUAGCCAGAUGUGUUGUGGGGGCUGGGGGGUGCCUGUAAUCCCAGCUACUCAGGAGGCUGAGGCAGGAGAAUCACCUGAACCUGGGAGGUGAAGGCUGCAGUGAGCUGAGAUGGCACUACUGCACUCCAGCCUGGGCAAACAAGAGUGAAACUGUCUUAAAAAAAAAAGAACAUAAAAAUGUACAUUUUACCCUCAUGUUCAAUUAUUUCAUUAAGGAGGUCACAAGUUUCCUCCUUGAGGAGGCGGGGAAAUCUUCAUUCUUUUACAUACUCCAAUUCUGGAGACAAGAUUUCAUUAUGUUGCCCAGGCUGGAGUGCAGUGGUGCAAUCACAGCUCACUGCAACCUUGACCUCUUGGGCUCCAGCUAUCCUCCCAUCUCAGCCUCCUCAGUAGCUGGAAUGACAGGUAUGCACCACCACGCCCAGCUAUUUUUUUUUUUUUUUUACUAGAGACAAGGUCUUGCUAUGCUGCACAGGCUCAUAUUCUCCCUUUCUACCUGGUCAAUGUCACCAGGAAUUUAUAUCAUUUUAUCCUAUGAUUAUUAGAAUAUGUUUAUAUAUGAAGAUAUAUUUAAUAGUUACUUAUUUCAUUUGAUAUCACAUAUGGAUAUGUAUGCACGUGUGUGUAAAAAUAUGUGUGUAAAGUCUCAAAAAAUAAUCAGAGGUUAUUUCAAUAAAACACAAUAAAACUUUCCUGAUUUGUCAUGACAAUUGUAUGCAGAUAUAAACUUUCUAAUAUCACAUCUUUAUAUGGAAGUAGGUAACAAUGUUAUUGAGAGAUCGUUGUUUAUUUCUUAAAAAUUAUGUGCGCUAAUGUAAAUGUUCAUAUGUAGAUGUAGGUAUUUAAAAGAUGGCAUAUAUUAUAAACAUAUUUAUUACAAUGACAAGUAAGAACAAUAUAUCAGAAAUUUUACAUAUAAAUACAGCACUAAAUUUACCUGAGUUUAAAAAAAAAAGAUUAUUAGGUCAUUGCCAUUAAUUUAAAAUAAUAAUUAUGUUUUGUUUUUACUGAGAUAAUUUUCUAAUUCUUACUUCCUUUUCCUUUUAUUUGAGUCCUUGGAUCUGUAAUUGCCUUGAAUUUUUUUGGCCAAUAAAAUUUUCAUGUCAGGUGCUUCUCUAAGAGGUGUUAUAAAUUUUUUCUCUCAAAGCUGACCCAAAUGGGCCAUGAGUUCACUUUUGAGACACAUUUUGCUACAAUACAGUCAUCUUGUCUUAGAGUUAUAUGUGUAAACAGCCUUAAGCCUAUAACUUUACUUAAAAUCACAUAUGAUUCAUUGGAUUUGAAGUUCAAGCUUCUUAAUUUUCUUUUUUUAAUCAGCUUUUUCAGGUUGAAAAAUCUUAAGCUCCAGAUGUAGUUGAGUUUGAUACCCACAUCAAAUAUCAUGUAGAAAUUGCGUGUUUUACCCCUGUAUACCAAAUUUGAAAAGAAAACAUCUUCCCAUUAUACCAGAGAGAAUAGUUUAAACUUAGUUUCCUCUCAUGCAUCAUGCUACACUGGAAUGUGUGACAUGCUGUGCCAAUAGACAUUACAUAUGGAAACAGGAGAGAACUUUGAAGAGCUGACAGAAGGCUAGAGUGACUAAAGCAGACUGUACAAAGCCAAGAGAGUGGUAGGCAGGUCCAGACUUCCUUGGUCUUGGGCUAUGGGAAAAUAGCAGUCAGAAAUAGACUUUCAGGACUUCAGCAUCAGCUAAGUGAAUAAGGAAUGGCCAAAUGCUUGAAUGGGGAGUAGGGGAGGAGACCAGUGCAUAUUUCAACAAUAUUAUCAUGUGACAGCAUUAUUUAAGAUGAUUUUAAGUUCAGUCAGGGCAAAUACACACACACAAACAUAUACGCGCGUGUGUGUAUAUGCAUAUGUAUGUAUUUUCUAGACACUUUCCUUCUUCCUCUUUGUCCUAAAUUUCCAUCUCUCAGGUGAACAGAAUUCUUAUUCUGCCUUCUUUAUAUUCAAGAACUCAACACUACAGCAUCCCACCGUUACCUCAACUACUCUCCUUACCCAAAUUAAAGUUAAAUCUAUGAGGAGUGUGUUAAUUUCCUAAGGCUGCCAUAAUAAAUAACCACAAACUGGGUGGCUUCAAACAACAAACAUUUAUUCUUUCACAAUUCUGGAGGCUAGAAGUCCAAACUGAAGGUGUCGAUAGUGUCAGGCUUUCUCCGAUGGCUCCAAAAAGAAUCAUUUCUUGCUCCCUCUAUCUUCUGGUGGUUGCUAGCAAGUUUCUUGGUUUGUGGCAGCUUAACUACAAUCUCUGUUUCUUCUUUAAUAGACUUCUUUCUGUGAGUCUGUGUGUCUCCAAAGCUCUCUCAUAUCACCAGUCAUUGGAUUUAGGGCCUAACCCUGUCCAGUGUGAUUUUCAUCUUUUUCUUUCCAUCUUUUCUUUAUUGACGUAUAUUUGAUGGAUGAAAAUUGUAUAAAUAAGAUAUACAGCAUGCUUUUGAUAUACAUAUACAUAGUAAAAUAAUUACUAUAAUAAAGUUAAUUGGUGGAUCCAUCUUAACUUGAUUGCACUGGCAAAUGAUGUAUUUCCCAAUAAGGUCCCAUUCACAGGUACCAGGGGUUAAGACUUCAACAUGUCUUUUAGGGGUGCCAUAAUUCAAUGCACAACAGGCGGCUAAUCUCAGCUAAGUGUUUAGAAGGACAACCACAUUAUCUGAUUAAAUCAAUUUACAUAAAAGUCAGAAUAACACUGCCUUUCUAAAGAAGUUUAUAACACAAAUGUACUGAAUAAUGUACACACUGUUAAGGGUAAGAGCAUUCCUAGUAACUGCUUUCUAUCCAGAGCUUUCAACUUUCCACCUUCAGUAAACUCAAGGCCAAGGUUAUAUUUCUCUACCCAUUUGCCAGAGUAGAUCAGCUACGAAAUGAAAAGGAUACUUAAGCAGAAAAUUUAGGUUGUGUAUGUUAUUUCCUUUUUCUUUAGUAAUGUUUUCACUUUUAGAGUAAAUAUUUUAAUAUUAUUUGACCAAAUUAUAUGAAAAAUGGCUUGAUACUUUAUUUUAAUUUUCCCAUGUUAAGAUGAAUUUAGAUCUGCAUAUUUGCCAUACAUGGUCCAUAUAUGAAGGAUAGAUAUAAAAUAUAUGAAGGACAUUGAUGAAAAAUGUUGGCAGUAGAAAACUACCCAAGUGUAAAUUAUUUUUUUUGUUUUGUUUGUUUGUUUGAGACGGAGUCUCGCCCUGUCGCCCAGGCUGGAGUGCAGUGGUGUGAUCUCGGCUCACCGCAAUCUCCGCUUUCCAGGUUCAUGCCAUUCUCCUGCCUCAGCCUCCCGAGUAGCUGGGAUUACAGGCGCCUGCCAUCACGCCCGGCACAUUUUUUGUGUUUUCAGUAGAGACGGAGUUUCACCAUCUUGCCCAGGCUGAUCUUGAAUUCCUGACCUCGUGAUCUACCCGCCUCAGCCUCCCAAAGUGCUGGGAUUACAGGCAUGAGCCACCGCGCCUGGCCACACAAGUGUAAAUUAUUUUGUGUAGUUUUCUACACAAAAUAGAAGGCAGGUACAGAUUUUUUGGCAGGUACAGAUUUUAUUUUUUCCAAAAUACAUUCUAAGUGUUUAUUAGAAGAACAAAUAAGAACAAAGAUAAAGAGUCAUCUCGAGGCUUCGUAUCAGGCAAUCUGGGUUCUUCCGUGCUUACUUAGAGUCAGAUUUAUUCAUAGUGGUGGAAUGCUCACGCCUCUAAGGAAUAAGUUCAGAAGAAUGUGGUACUUUUAUUUAGGCUAUUAAAAUCCUGAAAUUCAAGUUUUAAAAUGAUUCAAAAGGAGAUAAAUCUGUUUUAAAACAAAAUGCAUUUCUUUGUAUGCAGUGAGUCAGAGUACUGCUUUGUGGUAAAUUGCCUUAUGUUCUGAACAAUAUAAUGUAUUUCAUUUUUAAUAACUCAGUUUAUUUGUAAACCAUGUAUUAUUAACACAUAGCUCAAACUAUUGUAUUUAAUAUAGAAAUUGCAGUUAAAAUUGGAGUGGACUCUUUUUCUUUCCCAGAACAUUCAUUGUUUGAGGAGAAUUUAACAAGGCAUUUUGAUUUUUAAAAAUCCCUCAUCAGUGUAAGCACACCUUUAAAAUAAAAAUCAUAUUAUUCUAAAUUCAAUUGCCAUAGCAUAAAAUAGCUAUUUAAUAUUUUUGCUAGGACUAGUAUGUCUUCUUUGUUGAUUACAAAAUACAUACUAUGCUAAAUUUUAUCAUUUGAUUAUUGAUUUCCCAAGAGCCUUUUGUCUAAAUGAAAAGCUGUGUCUUAAGUUUUCUAAUUAAAAUUUAUAGUGAUAGAAUUAUUUUUCAUGCAGUUAAUUUAUACUCAAGAAGAGUUUUAACAGUUAUUUAAAUAAUGAUAAGUUUCUAUAGUUUUUUUAUUCAGUUGUUUUGAACACUCUGGAGCUGAUCUGUUAUUUUUCACAGCAUGAUUCCCAAACAUCUGCAACAAAUUCCUCUAAAAAUUAGGAACAUUGUUAGAUAUGGAAAUUCAGGAUCUUACCCGUACCUAUUAUCAGCAUCUCUGGAAAUAUACUUCAUAAAUAUCUGUUUCUAAUAAGCCAUUAGAUGAUUCUUAUGCCUAUUAAAUUUUAAGAACCCAGUGUUAAAGAGAACAAACCAGUGUAUCCUAACUUUUCUGACAUUAGUGAUCUCUAGACUUUGUAGUACAUUGGGAUAACCUGUUCAAUGAAUGUCAGCUUCUUGUAGAAGAAGUCAUCCAGGGGUCAGGAAAGAGAGAAAGCCUGAACUGCCUCUUACUACCCCUAGAGUUCUGGAGUUCUGGGAGCCUGACUGAAGAUAGCAGGCAGCAUGUAUGGAGCUAUGUCAAUGAGAAUGAGCCCAAGAUAAAUCAUCACAAUCCAUCAACCCUUCCUUCCUUCCUUCCUUCCUUCCUUCCUUCAUCUUCUUAAUGCUUCCUCUAUUUUUGUCAGAAGAAUUGGGAGGGAGGGUUAUUGGGAGAAGAGCAACAGCAUAUCAAAACCCUGCUUUAUCUUAUCUUGACGUCAUUUAACACUCUUAAAAAUAUGUGCUUUUAAAAGGAAGUAUUCAAUUUUUUUCUUGUUAUUGCCAUAGACAAAAAAUUAAUAAAGGGGUAUGAAGUGUCACCAACUGUCUGACCCUGGCCUACUUUCCCAAUCCCAGUUCCAAGAGGCAUGUACUUCUUGGUGGGUGUGACUGUUAUACAAUCUUUGGCUGACUUUACCUCUUAUCUCCUAUCUUCAGAUCCUUCUUCCUGGGAGGAUUUUAACAUGUAAGAUGAGGAAUUAAAACACCAUCUGAAUAAGUAUGAAGUGCAUUGCAGUCUUUGGAAGCAACAUGCAGAACUUAACCCAAACCUUAUUCUAUCCAUCAGAAGCUCCCAGGCUACUGACUGGUCUGUCUCUCCCAGGCCUGUUACAAGAAAAGUCAUGGCUUAUCAUUCAUCGGUUUAAUUAUUCCAAGACCCCCUUAGAGCUAGAGAAAUGAAGAGAUGGAGUGCUUAAACUUGAUUGAUUUGAUUGAAAGACACAAAGUAUCAAACCAUUUUUCAGACAUAUGUCUCAGUGAAAUUAAAAAAUAAAAAAAUUCAUUUUGGUUUAAACCAGAAUUUGGUAAACUACAGCACUUUAUGUAUGUCUGCCUUCAUAUUACAAAAGCAGAGUGAAGCUGAUGCAACAUAAAUUGUAUAAUAUAUGCGUACCUAUAGGACAUCUUUGAAUUUGCCUCCUGGCCUACAAUGCCUAAAAUGUUUACCAUAUGGAUCUCUAGGGCAUAGCUUUGCUAACCUCUGGUCUAAAUGAAAACAUUCAUGAUUUAUUUUCUCCAGCAUCUGAAGGCAAAAUAUGCAUCCACCGUAUUCCAUAAAAAAUUAUUCAUACAUGUCUUAAAACUUGCAUAUUUUAUUUUCUAACCCCCAGCAUAAGACAACCAUAAAUGUGUAGGAACAACAGCCUUAGCCCCAACAACCACAACAGCACCUAACAUAAUAGGGAUUCCAUAAAUGUUUUGAUUAAAUAAGUCUUUAAAAAUAUAUGUACAUUCUGCAUUUUAUUUACGAUAUACUGUCUCUCUAUUUUAGAACAAAUUUCAUUUUCUCCAAUCUUUGAAUAAAAUAGAUGCUUUAGGAAGAAUGUACAAGGAGAUUUCUAGUACUGCUUAAAGCUCAGGAGAAGAAGCUCAAGAAUUUGUCCUGAAGUGUGCAAGUUUUAAAAGAACAAAGCAGCUUUCCCUUCCCCGAAAUACAUGUUGAAAAUAUUUCUAUCGAUAAAGUAUAUGUAUAAAUUUGGACAAAUCUAUGUCAAACAUCUAUUAUAACCAUUACUAAUCUGUAUUCCAAGCAUAAGUGUAUUUUAAGUUCUUAAGACAUUGAUGUUUGUCAAUGGUCCUAAGUGUUACUAAUUCUGUCGCCUCCAGCAACUCAGCAUGUAGAACAGACUAUAUCAUUCAAGGCUAGCCUUCUACAGAACAUCCAACCCUGUUCAACUCACGAGGAUCUACAUCCUAUUCACUUUAACUAUAGAGUCAAGACAGAUCAUUCAAGUGAGCUAAGUGAGAGAGAAGGAAUAAGAAGAAAGCACAACCCUUGAAAGAUUUCAGAUAAUGAAAAUAAACAAGAGCUGUAGAAGUAAGUACAAAUCAUGCACGUCUCUCAUGGCCACUUUUUUUUUUUUUUUGUCAGAUAUUGCAAAGCUAUGGACCUGGGGAGAUGACCUUUAAAUCAUCUAGCUCAGAAUUUGUUCCACAAUAAAAAGCUUAAGAAAUGUCCAUUAUUUCCCUCCCUUCUUCUCAUUCAUUCUCACUUGGCUUUGUUCUUUUCAGUCUAGGAUUCUUAUUCAUAUUUCUACCUAAUGUAAAGAGCCAACCAACAUUUUUUGGACUGUGAGGGGAAAAUUUUCUUUUCCAUGUACAUUUAUGAAAAAGAAAUUAUUUAGAGCCAAAUCAUCCCAUGUUGUAUGCAAGAGGCAGACACAUCACACCAAGAAUGAGACUCUGGAAUCAAUCUGUCUGGGUUCCAGUCCAGCUGUACCACUUACAAGCUGAAUGACCUUGGACAAAUUGCUUAACCUCUCUGUGCAUCACAUUUCUCAUCUCUAAAACUGGAAUAGUACUACUUCAUAAGCUCGUUGACAGGACUGAAUGAGAACAUAUAUGUAUAGAACCCUUAAAAUUGUGCCUGUAUAUAGUGAACACUCUUUUAUCACUACGUGUUAUUAUUAUUAGCGUUAAUGAGAAUCAAGCUCUCAGCAUGACCCAGGGGUUCUCCAGCUCACCUUCACUGCCUUGUGCAUGUCUUCCAUUACACUCUCUACCACUCUGUUCCACAGAGGCCAAUAUGAUAUUAGUCCUAAAAUGACAUUAUCCUUGUUAUGCUUAUCUUUGCUCAUGCUGAAGUGCCUUGUCGUUAUUCAGUAUUCACUUUGCAUAACCUAUUUUCCAUUAAGCUUCCACCUUGCAAAAUAGAAUGCCACUACAUUGUACCCGAAGCCAGACACACACACACCGUUCAUUUGUACACACACAGUUCAUUUGUACACACACAGUUCAUUUCUCUUUUUCCCCUUCCACUUCUAGAUUGUGAAGAUUUCAAGGGCAGAGAGAGAGUGUUAGGAACCCUUAUGGCCAUAACCCCUACCAACUCUCUGUUACAUAGAAGACAUUUAGAAAAUGUAUGUUGAAUUAAAAAAAGCUUAAAGACCAGUCAUAAAAUUUUGAUUUCAUAAAAUUCUACUUAAAGUAUAGCCACAGGAUUUGGCUCCAUGACCUCUUUUGGCAGCAAUGCUCACUUAUUAUCAUAAACAGCACAUAGUACUUGUCAUUAUUUUUCAAAAUUCAAUGUCCUUUAAUGUCAUCUGGUCAGCUGAAUUAAGAAGCUUGCUUCUAUUAAUGGAAUUCAGUUUUCAAUAUAUCUGAGGUGUUUCUAACAACACCAUUCAGAGUUCUCUGAAGCUUCUUUUUAAAUAAAUAAUGCUCCAUUUGGUCAUUUCUUUGUUCUUUUAUAUUUAUAGAUUGUAUAGUGUUUUUCUUAAUCAUUUGCACUAACUUUAAUUCAACAGCAACUGAAAACAAUUAUAUAAAACUAGUGUGUCUCCAUAUUCUUCAUCUUUGGUGAAUUUUUCCCCAAAUUUACUAAAGUAUCUUGCAUAAAGAUCUAUAUUUUAUUAUUUAAACUGACCCUUCUCUACAAAAAAAUUACUCAACAAUGAUUCAAAAAUGAUGACUCAAUGAUGCAUUUGUGUUUGUGAAAUGACCAUACUAAUGAAUUGGAUUUAAUACUUUAUUCAAAUAUAUCAAAUGUAUUGCAAAUCCAAACACUUAUUUCCACCAAACCUAACAACCACCAUUGUCUCUCAAUUCAAGGACAGUAAUAGCCUUUGAACUGGCUACUGCUUCCAGGCUUGCCCCUCUAUUGUCAACAGAACAGUUGAAGUGAUCAUUUAAAAUUGUAUUCAGAUCAUGCUAGUUCCAAGCCAAAACCUUCUCGUAUCCAUUGCACUAUAAAGUCUAACUCUUUACAAUGGCCUUUGAGGCCCAUCAAGACCUGCUGCUGCCUGGCUGUCUUACCCUUCCCCUCACACCCAGAGCACUAUGGGUGUGAGGGGAACUAUAGCUACAGGUAUACUGGGGUGUUUUUCUUUUUUGUUUGAACAUGCAGUGCUUGUUACUGUCGUGGGACUUUGCACUUUGUGUCUACUCUCCUUGUAAUGCUAGAUCUUGAAUAUAAGGCUGAGUCAUUGUCUUCAACUCAUACAUGACCUCCUUCAUGAAAUCUUCCUUUUCUGGCUGCUUCUCUUCAGUGGGCCUUUCCAUCAGGUGCUGGCAACUCUCAGUCAGUUCUUUCUCAGCUCUGUCUCUUCUAAUGGCCUUGCUAAUUCAGCCUGCCCUUGAUCUUGGUGCUCAGAUUCCUCAGAGUCUCUACUACUUUUCUCUUCUGACAUCUGGUUAAAGCUGCGAGCCUCAUAAACGUUUUUGGCUGAGCCAUUUUGCUCAUAGAAGGCCCAUUUAUCCCCCUCAACUUAUUAUCCAUAUUGCAUGAUAGCUAAAGGAAACUUGGGAUUGCAAAGUGAAUCUGUCAUGCCACAGGGCCUCCUUGACUGCUACUUGGGAUCCACAUGUUAGCUUGGGAUUACUCAGCACAGUAAUGUCCUCCAAAACUUGAAAGCAAAAACCCUGAGCAUCCCCUCAACUUAAUUAAGAAUUUCAAAAGAUACAUCCCCUAGAGGAUUGGCCUCGACAAGCUGGGAAGAAAAAACAAGAGCGGUGGCAGCCACUUUUCUCUACCAUUGAGCUCUUUCUCUCCACCUAUUCUGGCAUUUCUCAAAAGAAUGCCUGAAGGCUUUUUUCCUAUUGUGCAUUUUUUAAGGGUAUCAUUCUGUUGCCAAGGCUGGAGUGCAGUGGCAUGAUCAUCUAUAACCUCAAACUCCUGGGCUCAAGCAAUCUUCCCACAUCAGCUUCCUGAGUAGCUGGGACUACAGAUUUAGAAUGUAAUAACUCAAGGAUUUGAUAAUACAGUGAAGUAGUAUAACAACUGUCUACGUGCUUCCCAUGAUAUGUUCUCUAUAUUGACCUAAGGAACAUAGUUGGUAAUACAGAAUCCUGUGGAACUCCAAUAAUUUCAGAGAAAAUUGAGGAUACAGUAUUUUUACCCUCUGCACCUGGAAGAACUUACUGCUUUAUUUUGGAAAAAUUAUGACAUCAACAUCCAAAGGAAUUCUUCGCCCAUUUUUAAUUGUCUGCAUUAUCCUGGGCUGUUUCAUGGCAUGUCUUCUCAUUUACAUCAAACCUACCAACAGCUGGAUCUUCAGUCCAAUGGAAUCAGCCAGCUCUGUGCUGAAAAUGAAAAACUUCUUUUCCACCAAAACUGAUUAUUUUAAUGAAACUACUAUUCUGGUGUGGGUGUGGCCAUUUGGGCAGACCUUUGACCUUACAUCCUGCCAAGCAAUGUUCAACAUCCAAGGAUGCCAUCUCACAACGGACCGUUCACUGUACAACAAAUCCCAUGCAGUUCUGAUCCAUCACCGAGACAUCAGUUGGGAUCUGACAAAUUUACCUCAGCAAGCUAGGCCACCCUUCCAGAAAUGGAUUUGGAUGAAUUUGGAAUCACCAACUCACACUCCCCAAAAGAGUGGCAUUGAGCACUUGUUUAACCUGACUCUGACUUACCGCCGUGAUUCAGAUAUCCAAGUGCCUUAUGGCUUCUUGACGGUAAGCACAAAUCCCUUCGUGUUUGAAGUGCCAAGCAAAGAGAAAUUGGUGUGCUGGGUUGUGAGUAACUGGAACCCUGAGCAUGCCAGAGUCAAGUAUUACAAUGAGCUAAGCAAAAGCAUUGAAAUCCAUACCUACGGGCAAGCAUUUGGAGAAUAUGUCAAUGAUAAAAAUUUGAUUCCUACCAUAUCUACUUGUAAAUUUUAUCUUUCCUUUGAAAAUUCAAUCCACAAGGAUUACAUCACGGAAAAGCUAUACAAUGCUUUUCUGGCUGGCUCUGUACCUGUUGUUCUGGGACCAUCUAGGGAAAACUAUGAGAAUUAUAUUCCAGCAGAUUCAUUCAUUCAUGUGGAAGAUUAUAACUCUCCCAGUGAGCUAGCAAAGUAUCUGAAGGAAGUCGACAAAAACAAUAAGUUAUACCUUAGUUACUUUAACUGGAGGAAGGAUUUCACUGUAAAUCUUCCACGAUUUUGGGAAUCACAUGCAUGUUUGGCUUGCGAUCAUGUGAAAAGGCAUCAAGAAUAUAAGUCUGUUGGUAAUUUAGAGAAAUGGUUUUGGAAUUAAAAUUUUUCAUCACUUGCACACUUGAUAAAUAUUUUGAUGAGAUAUCAUCCAAGUAUUGAGGAUAAGAAGAGAUGCAACAUACUACUUUUGUGUCACAAUUUAUUUUUAUCACCCUCUCUAGGGUAACGUGUAUAUUUUGGUGGAGAUUUUUAAAAGCUCAGCAUGAGCAAUCAUUCCAUUCGGUUUUAAAUUAUCCUGUAUAUACCUAAUUAUGUGCACUGGAGAGUAAUUUAUUCUUCAUUAUCAUUUGUAAACAUUGUUUUUUCACAUUUUUGUAGUUGUCCAUAAUGUAAGCUUGUGGUUUGAUUAUUGUUUCCACACUGAUCAGCUGUUUAAUCUAUUUGGGAAAUGAAGAUGCACAUCUUAAAGUAUGAAAAAUUUUCACUAAGUAUUACAAUGUCUAGUUCCAACUUUGCAUACUAUAACAGAGGAAGAACAUGUUGCGAUUGAAUUCUAACCUCUUUGACUCCGAAGAUGAAUGAAGUGUAUAACUGUCUCUAUUUGAUCUAUUUUUUUUACCUGUUUAUCACAUUUGUGAAGGUGAAAUUAUUCAUGGAGUGAAUAAGAAAGAUAUGAAGCAGAACUGUUCUAUUCGGGAAGCUAUUAGACUUCUCAUUUAUUUUCAUUAAGCUGAUUUGCAGCUACUUAUUCUCAUGGUCUUAAAUUAAAUUAUUCAAGUAUUUUUAAAUAUCCAAUUUGUUGUGAUUUUCAGCACCUGGGAAGUAAUCCCAAUAAUACUUUAGAAAAUCUAAGACAGUUCUUUCUGCUACUGAUGACACUCAUUGUCAUAAUAAAACAAAUAAUUUCCUCAAAUAACAAAGAAAAAUGAUACCUAUAAAUAUAUUUAUAAAUGGUGUCAUUUAUGAACAAUGUUUAAUUAUGUAUCAAUUUAAGAUUUUUUUCUGAAGCCCUAAUAUUUAAAAUGGUCUUAUUUUACCAUAUGGAUAUAAGAUUUGGCUCAUAAUGAUGAGCCCUAUCAUUUGAUUUGAGUUCUAUCAUUUAAGAGAGCCUAAAUAAAAUUAUCAUCAAGGUAUUAAAUAUAAGACGUUAAAUAUAAUAAAGUGGGGAUAUAUAGAAAACACACAGUGUUAGCACACAGUAAGAUCUCAAUGCACAUUUGUUGGAUGAAUAAAUAAAUGCAAUUGAAUUCCCAGAAAAAUGAUUGUUUCAAGGAAGUGACAGUUCUACUUUAGAAGUACUAAUUGGAGAUGACUUUUAUAUCCCAUUUUGGUAAUUAUUCAUACAUAGCACAUAUGACCAUGAUGUUCAGGGCUUUAUAGAACCAAAUAAACCUACCAUUACAUGAAAAUUUUGAAGAGUAUAUUCCUGAACUUGCAGCUGCCUAUAGCAUUCUCCUCCAUAAGGCUAGAGGAGAGCUGGAUAUAAGCAGAGAUCGUAGGUGAAAAAAGAUGGGCCAUUAAGGAUUCUUCAAGGAAAACAUUCCUCAAAAUGAUCUUUAGUGCCUUUAUUCCUUUCAGGCCAAUAAUCCACCCAAAAAUUAGAAUGUUCUGAGACAUCCAUUUGGGUCUAUUUGUGACUUAUUCGUAUUACAAAUUGACAUCAGCAAAAUUCAAAAAGAAUUCAGUAAAAAGGGCAUAGAUCCAGCUAUCCAGACUAUCUUGUGAGAGAAUAAGCUCACCCCAGCACCAGAAAGAUUUGAGCAGAGGAAUAUUCCUGUAAUGAAUAGAGGAUUGUUUGAUUCUCAGGUAUAUUUCUUAAGCCAAGAUUGAAUGCAGUGUCAGGCACUGCCUUAACACCCACAGAGAUAAGAUGAACAAGGUACUAUCACUGCCUAAAAUGAGCUUACAAUUAAGUGGAUAGACAUAUAAAAGCUUCCUUUCAAUUCAGCCUGAGACUGUUUAUAUGCAUGUGCUACUCCGAAUGACGUUUGUAUGGGUCAAUGCUGAUUUAAUGGGGAAAAAAAGUAGAAAAUUUCCCCAAUUGCUUAGCUGUUUGACAUGUUUCUGAGCUGCAAACUUUGUCAACUCUUUUGACCCAACAUAUUAUUCUCUCCGUAUUAUCUCUUCUAACCACAAUGCAUUAAGAAAUAAUAUUUUUAUGUGGAUGUCCUCCUCAAUAAGUAAAGAUCUCCAUCCAUAUUUAAUUAAUUGGUAAGACAGUCAAAUUCAUACAUUUACAUUUACUUUGUCAAAUUUUUUGGUCUAUAAAAAGCAUAGAGAUCUAAAGAGGAUACACUGCUAACAAGUUUAGAAAGCACCUGCUUUUUUUUAUUAUUAUUAUUUUUGUGAUAGAGUCUUGCUCUGUCGCCCAGGCCGGAGUGCAGUGGUGCAGUCUCGGCUCACUGCAACCUCGGCCUCCCAGGUUCAAGUGAUUCUCCUGUAUCAGCCUCCCGAGUAGCUAGGAUUACAGGCGUGUACCACUAUGCCUGGCUAGUUUUUGUAUUUUUAGUAGAGAUGGGUUUCACUGUGUUGGCCAGGCUGGUCUUGAACUCCUGACCUCAAAUGAUCCACUUGCCUCAGCCUCCCAAAGUGCUGGGAUUACAGGUAUGAGCCACUGUGUCUGGCCCACCUGUUUUUUUUGAAGGCAGAAAAACAUUCAAUAUUAAAAGCAUUCAAUAUUAUUUCAACCUGCCUUGGCUCUAGUGAAUGUUCAUGAUUUGAAAGAACUGAAAGACCUAAAGGCAGUGUCUCUAUUGUUGACUACAAAUGUAGGCUCUUUGUUGGACUAUGACUAUAAUCACACACUGAUAAUAUGACGCAAGUAGAGGCAGUACUACUAAGUAUCUAGCAGGUGCUUUGAAACCCCAUUACUAAGUCCCAGAAGACUGUUUCCUAAAUUUGAAGUGGAAGAAUUAAAUGACUCAAUGGAACCCUUUAGCUGUGGGUCCAUUGAUGUGUGAGUUUUAGAGCUGGAAGGAAUUAUAAUUUUGUUGUUUAUAAUUGCUAUAAUAUAGAAAUUAUAAUUGCUUUUCUUUCUACUUAUGAGUUAACUAGAUCCAGAGAUAUUUAUUCAAGACACACAUUCACACACACAUACACACACACACACACACACCCCACAGCUAGUGACAAUAGUUAAGAUUUGGAUUUAAGGAUCCUAUCUUUCUUUAUCCCACUUUCUUUUCAAUCGCAUUCAUAACUUAUUAUAGAAUUAUGUCUCAAUUUUUACAAAUGUGAAUGUCUUAUUGGUAUUUUUAGGGCCUAUAGAAUGGUACACCUCAUGUAGAAGAACUUCGACUUUUGAAGGUAUACAAUAAAUAAAACAUCAAACUUGUUAGCAUUCGUUCUGGUUUAAAUAUUUUAGGAGUUGAGUUCAGCAGAAGGAAAUGGGCUAUCACUACAUUUAAGUGAAAUACAACCCUCAAGAAAGUGUAUGGUUCACAGCCACUCCUUUAAUAAAUCCUGUGGGUUGCAAUUCUUUGUAAGAAACUCAUGAAAAAGAUAUAUUGAUUCAACAAAAUUGGUUUGCUGUUGAUUAUACAAACCAAUAAUUAUGCCUAGAAUUAAAUUGUGGACACAAAAAAGGGAACAGACCAUUUAAAAUGUUUUAUUUCAAAAUAUCGAAAAGCUAUUACCUUCAAUACUCUAAAUAUUUAAAUAUUAAUUAUUGUAGACAUCAGUAAGAAUAAAUAAAUGUUAAUCAUUAUAGACCUUACUAAUAAGAAUAUAUACUGAAUUGUCCACAUCCAGAGUAUUACACCCUGAACAAGAAAGACAUGAGAGCCUGACAGUCAUAUAUAUUAUGACAGCUGUAUAUCUGACAAUAUGAAGUAGAAACUGAAAAAAAAAAUCAUCUUAGUGGGAAACAAAUACAUGCUUAAAAUUGUUAUAUUUACUGUAAAACUCCUGAUAAUCUUAGAUUGUGCAGAAAUGUUUCUUAUUUUGAGGGGCUUAGAAAGCUCAGCGCAUUUGAUGUAUAAAGCAACAGAAUAUUUAGGAAUUAUUUGCGGAGGCUUUAAAUUCUUACCUCCAAUUGGAGGUUAAAUAUUAAAAGAAUAGGAAACUAUGCCUCUGAUAUUUUUUUUGUCAGCCUAUUUUUAAACUAGAUUCCAUGAGUCUUAAGGUAAUAUCCUAGAAUUUUUUUUUUGCGUGAAUUAAAGUUACCACAAAUUUCAGGUCCUUACCUUAUGACUGUGUUUGAUCAUAUCUUUGAGUUCCCUUGAACUCUGAUCUCAUUUUGAGAAACAUUUUGAGAAACUUCUUAACAAUUACAAUCGAGCUGUUAAAUAUAACAAACAUCAGAAUCUAAAGGAUAAGCACAGUGCCUAAUGUACAGGAGGGUCAUAUCAAAUACUUGUUGAAUAAAUACAUGAAUGUGAUAAGUGGUCCUGUAAAAUAUUUUUUAAGAGUAGUGACAAUGUUUAUUGGUACCAAUUGGAGAUGAUAUUUUAUAUUUAUUUUGUUAGUUUGUCACCUGGAUGCAAAAGGAAGGCAUUUUAAUUCCUUUCUAUCUUACAACAUUGUAAAGCAUCAAAAGAAGUAACAUCUCAAGAAAGAUUAGAAAGGAUUUGGAUCACGUUAACAUUCUAUGCAAAUAUUAGUAACAUAUCAACUGUUUCUAAAAGGAAAGAAAAUUAGUAUUUAAGGAGAGUAUAAAGUGCGAGCACUGUGAAGGGCAGAUAUCUAUUACCAAACCACAUGGAGAGAAAUAUAGUCUCUCUCCUAACUUCAUUCCAUUGUAUUGCAAUCAGUCAAUUAAGGUGAUUUUUUUUUUCUGGAUGUCUCAAUCUAGAGAUUUUGUAGCAUUUUGCAAAUGGGUAUGCUUCACUACUAUCCACAGUGUUCUCCCCUUUAGUAAUUCAUAUUGAAUAUAUCCAUAUUCAUAUGCAUUUUAUAAAACAGUUAACAGAAUCUAAAUAAGAUAUAGCCGGCUAAAUCUGGAAUGUGAGUGCUACCCUAGGUUAUUAGUUCAACAAACUAAUUUUGAGAGAGCCACUUAACCUCUCUGGACCUUGUUUGUAAGCUUUCUUCUAGCACUAUUACUCUUAUCUAAGAUCGAAAUUGAUAUAUGCAUGAAAUUCCUAAUGGAAUUUCAAUGUCCAUCUCAAAGUAAUUUUUUAGGAUAUUCCAUACAGAUUUCCUUCUCAUUUCUCUGUGUAGAUAUUUAAAGUAUGAAAUUGAUUAUUUAAACUAAUAUGUGGAAAGAACCUAAUCCAGAGCUUGGAAUAUAGAAAGUGCUCAAUUAACUGACAUUCCUCCUGUAUUUCCUCCCUCCCCUUAGUUGUCUAUGACUUUUGAACUCACUGCUCACUGACAUCUUAAUUGCCUGCAGAAAAAUCAAUCAUAUUUUAGGCAUUAUUUUGAAAUAUUUUAGAGUUUUCUGUACUAUUCAAACUCUUAUUACAAAAAUCUAAAGAUAUUUAUUGAUGCAAAAAAUUUAGGGAGUCAUUGGAAAUACCUGAGGCAAUCCCAGGCUAACAAUAAAAUAGCAUAAUUUUAAGUAAGCUAGAUUGAGUUCAUUUGAACAUUUAGUUAUUUUUUAGCUCAUAGUUAACAUAUGUCCAUGCAUUUGAUUUACUUUAAAAAUAUUUUAUUUAAAAAUAACCUCUCAAACACCAGUUGCUUUCUGUCAGUUUUACUCAAAGCAUGCUUCCUAGGUCACCUGACCUAGAAUCACCAGAAGUGUUAACAAUACCGAUUUCUGGGCUUUGAGCCAUGAAAUUAGAAUUUCUUCAAAUAAUCCAUGCCCCCCCGUCACCCAAAAAAAGAGCAUGCUUUUAAUACAUUUCCAAAAUUAUCCUGUUUCUGCUAUAACUGGUGAACCAUCCUGUCCUAAACUAGCAGUUCUCAAACAUGCAUAUGCCUUUGAAACUUCCUAGAUCAUCUACAUAAAAAUCAUUUGAAAUAUUGUUAAUAAUACACAGCUUCUGAAUCUCUGGGUGUGAGAUGGGACCAGGAAUCUUAUUUUAAAAAUCUCCCCAGAUGGUUCUGGUGUCCUGCUAGUUUUGAGGUUUUCAUCCCACCUGUUUAGAUGGGUAGUAUUCUAUUAAAUAUGAGGUAUUACCUUUCUUUAGUUCACCUGGAAUCUUCUUAAAUAUAUCGGUAAAGUAUUCUACUUCAAAAUCCAAGACAUUUUGUAUACCUAAUUAUUUCACACAAGAGCGUGGAACUCACCAGUCUUGUGACUUGGGGCAGGUUAUUUAUAGUCUCCAGACACUUUUUCCAGUUGCGAGUUGCUUAUAGUAGUUCGCGAACCUGAAUGCACAUUAGAACCAUCUGGAGAGGCUUUAAAAUUGCAGAUGUCCAAACCCCACCUCCAGAGAGCUGAUCUAUUUAGUUUGAGGAAGAGCCCAGAAGUCUAACAGGUGUAAAUGUUCCACAGGUAAUACUAAUGCAGGCAUACCUCAGGAAAUCACCAGUUCUCGUCUUGGAGGAACUAUUAGGAAAAUAAAAGAUUAUAUAUCUUGAAAAAAAUCUCUAAUUUGCUUUCUAGGUUCUAACUGCAUGUUUAUAUUUUGCAACAGGAAAGACUGGUCUAGACAAUUACUAGGAUAUAUGCUUCUGUGAUCUGCUUUUCUAUUGUAUGUGUUUAAGAGACCACAUUCUUGGGUUCCAAAGUCUCCUUGUCUGAUAGGUAAUUUGCAAUUGAGAUAUGGCAAAGAAUUGUAGCAUCCAAAUUUUUGACAACUACAGAUUUAGAAUUGAAUCCAAGGUCUGCCAUUCACUAGCUAUGUGCAAGUUACUCAACUUCUCUUAUCCUCAGAUUUUGCAGCUGUAAAGCAGAGGUAGCAUAUUUCUGAGAAAUUAUAUUCAGGUGACUAGAUAUGUGUUCAAGUGUUAUCUUUUAUUCUUAUAAAAGAUAAUUGUGAGGAAUCCAGUGCUAUUUUCACAAUUUUAAUUCUAAAACUCUGAAGACAUUAAACAGGCAGUUUGUAGGAAUCAUUGAAAUUUUAUACAAGCCGAAGGAACAACAUUCAGCAAAACGGAAACAAAUAAAUACAGCAUGGAAGCAUAUAUUCAUGUUUCCCAUAAUUACUAAGUUACGGAAGGGGUGUGAGGAGCUGGCAGUGGUGGUGAAUAGGCAUUGUUUGCAUUACUAAAUAUAUAUACCAUUUCUUAAGAUAAUUGGAACUCAAGCAGUCCUAAUUUUCUCUCCCUGUUAUGAGCAAUCAGUAAAUUUGUAGUCAAUUUAACUUAUUAUCAGUUGGUAUAGCGCAUGUCACAGAAUAGGAUAGCAAGAAGAUUCUCAGAGAUCAUUUUCUGGUAAAGAAAAAGGCCUAGCAAUAUUUAACAGUUUGACUUAAUCCAUCACUUCAGCUGGUCCACUAGUUUUGACACAGGACUAGUUAAUGAUUUGUUAGGAAGUCUCCAUCUACUCUUAAACUAAUUUAAAAAAAAGCUAAAAGUUGCUUUUAAUAUGUUAGGGUAUAACUUCAAUAAACAGGAGUAUUUAUCUAGUGGUUCAGAAAUAAAAUAAUUGUUAGCCAGCCUGUGAUUAAGGCUACCAUAAUUGCAUAAUAAAUAGCUUUGACGUGAAUAAUCUCAGUUGUUCAAGUGUACAAAUUUAAAGCUGUACUAUGUUAGAAUAAAAAAGUAGGCUCAAGGAAAAUUUCUAUUUUUCUAUAUGAAAAAGAGAAUGAUAUUCAAAAUAGUAUUUUUAAGUAGUUUCUAAUUGUGUUCCUUUAAAGAGUAUUAGAAAUGUCUGUUAUGUCAGUAACAUUAGAAAACUUCAAAAACUGAUUUAUUUUUCUGAGUUCUCUGGAAACCAAACAAUUUUGAAUUAGUUGUGUAAGUAAAGUAAGUUAAGUUAUAGCUUGCUGGAAUUUUAUUGUGGAAAACAAAUAUAGAUUUUAUCUGAAAAAUUUUAAGGGCCAAUUCUACAGAAAGUUAUGCUAACAUGCUAACUUUCCACACAUGGCUGCAUUCCAUUUUGAUUAAUGAGGGUUCAGGAAAUAGAAAGGCAGUCUCUGCAGAAGCAGUAUCCAAAGGCUAAAUUAACAACCCAGGACUACCACUCAUUAUGUGAGAAAUAUGGGCCAGAGUUACAAUAUCACAUCUCCAGUCUCAGAUUGGCCUCAUUAGCCACCUUCAGUUCCUUAAAUGAGAUAAUCCUGAAGAUGCCAUCCUUGUCCAAGGUGAGAUUGCCAGAGGAUAUGAGCUCAUCUAGGAUGGAAUACAUGUCUCCAGGGACUGUAAUGAGAUCAGGCUUUUCAUUUACUGGUUUUCUGCCUCAAGAGUCCUUAAGCAAAUGAAGAUUAUCUGAUUGUCUAUGUAAACCUGGAAGUAGUCUACUUUUUAGAUAAAAGAUAAUCUAUCUUGAAUAUUUCAUAUGUGAUUUUAAAAUAAUUAAUCAAAAAACAAAGACUAUCAUAUUUGAGAACAAGAUUUUACUUAGAAGGGAAAAAAAAGAACUUUCAGCUUAAUCGGGGUUAAGGGAGUAAUUGUGACAAUAUAAAAUGGCAUUGUUAUAGAAUCCCUAAAAGGUAAAUAAUGUAUGAGAUGAAGGUAGGAAGUAAUGUGUGCUUGCAGAAAUGCAACUGGUCAAAAUUACUUGAAUGAAAUUGUUGAGGUUAAACAUCUUCAUUAUAAUAAUAUGUCUUAUUCUGAUUCCAAGACAAUACGAAUGUAGAGAAGAGAUUUUUAAAUGGAAAAAGUAAGGAGCUAACAAGUCUGUACCUAGAUUCAAGUUCACAAAGCGGCAAAAAGGAGAAAAGUGUCAACAAGAAACAAGAAGAGGAGUAGUAAACUAAGGAUCAAAGCCCAAGUUCCAGUUUUCACAAUCUGCUGUAUAAUUCACUAACAUUUCUGAGCCAUAGAUUUUUAAUCUGUAAAAGGAGUGUGAUGGACUGUACAUUAGAAGUACCUGAGAAGCUCUUAAUAAAUCUUGAUGAAUUGGUUAGAAAUUCUAAUUUAAUUAGCCUGGCACAGUGCACAAACUGCCAUAUAUUCGUGCAGAUGUUUUCUUCUUUUCUUACUGCGCAUUUCCAUGUGGCCAUGUCACUACAAGGGGUGGGGAAGAAGUUAAUGUGUAAUUGCUUCAGGAGCUCUGAAUAAAAGGUUGCUGAAGCAAAAUACUGCAAUGAAGUUCUGAAAAUGAAGAGUUAGGACUUUACAUGAUUUCUCUUGCCUCAUUCCCUCAAGAAUGCACAUAUAGACACACAUAUGCCAAUAUCUUUUUUAUGUAGUUCAAGUAUAACUUUGAAUAAAAUGACUUACAUUCAAGGAAGGUCAAAACUAUUAUUCUGAAACAAAAUGUGACAAUUCUAGCCAUUAUGUGAAUUGUAAGGGUCAGUAAUCCAUAAAUUAUUUGGAUGGUAAUUGUAUGUUUUAUUAAUGUGAUGUAAUUUUGCACUAUUGUAUUGUCAUAUUUAAUCAAACUCUUAAAAAUACCCUGAAACAUAAUGCCAAAUGUACAGUUUAUAGGUUCGUGUUAUUUCUGAUAAGAAUUUAAUUGCAUUGUGCUAAUAGUUGUUUAUUGCUAUUAACUUUCUGUGUAUGUAUUAUUGCGAUGCAGACCCAAUAGGGUUAUUUUAAGCACACUAAUUAGUCAUCUGGAUUUUUAUAGAUAAAAUCACAUGUUGAUCAGAAAUCAUUUUUCUACUUAUUUUUUUGUAGAGUAUUUUUCCACACUUGAAAAAAACAUGAUUAUUUUAUAUCAAACAUCAACUUUUCUUUAAAUCUUAUUUUAGUAGCUAAUGCAUGUUUGAAAUAAGAUGUGUUAGAAAUUAUAUGACUAUAUUAAGGUUGUGUUUAUAUUAGGUGAAAAAUUGCAUGCAAUUGGUGAAUCAUGCAGCUUUGGGGACAUUUACACUGCCACUCACACACAGGCUCUGUCUCAAUCCGUAUGCAUGAUUCACGUCCUUUCAAAAGUCCCUUUUCAACAUUUGGUAAAGUGAAAAUGUUAUUCAUAGUGCUAAUGAGCCAAUAAACAAUGCUGCGUUUCUUUUUUCUAACUGCAGCAUAUUGUGGUAAAUUUUCUCCCAAAACUUUAUUUUUGGAGUUAUUGUUGGCAAUAAAUACAACAAAUUAUUUGUUGGCAAGUGAUACAAUUUACUGUAUAACAACUUAAUAGUACAAAGCAUGAAGAUGUGAAAAUAUCAUCUUAACCAGUUUCAUUCUAUGAACAUAAUAUUCUGGCAGCUUUUUCUAUAACUGAGAAUGGUAUAUCUUUUUAUACACUGCCUAAAUCAGUACUACUGCCAGUCACCUGAGGUCAGGUCUGCACAACACUAAAUUGGGCAAUAACAUAGAACAUCUAGGCAGUCUUGACAGUCAACCAGUGUAAUCACUAGGGGAAGAAAAAGUAGGCCUACCCUUUUACUUAUUAACUUAAGUAAUAAAAAUUGUAUAAAAAUAUGAAUGUUGGCUGCAGAGGAGCCUUUACAUGCAGAUAAUUUGAAGCAGUCUUUGAAAAUAACAAAAAUUAUUCCAUUUAAUGAAGGGUUUGUUUUGUUUAGCUUUUCUCUUUUAUUCAGAAAACAUACCUGUGCUUUUGAAAGGGCUUAAUCCCAAACAGGUAAUAUGUGUGGAUCAAUCAUCUCUCCUCCCAUGAAAUUAAUCAUUCAUGGUAAUAUAUUAAGGCUGGAACGUAGCUCUUAGUGACUUAAAACAUGACAGUAAGCAUUUACACUGUUGGAAGGUAAUUUCAUUGCUAUGUUAUUAAAAUGAUGGGAAUCCUAUUUAUACAUUUAUUUAUUUAUUUAUUUACAGAAGAUUGGUUCCUUCCAGUUCAAUUUAACAGCUUCAGUGAAGUUAGUAUAAUGAUAAGAAAAAUUGACUGUAGCUAUUAUUCCAAGUGAAAAUCAUGCAGCUGAGUCCUGCUGCAUCCUGGGAGCAAAGCAUUAAUUCAAAUGAGGAGUAGUCAGUCCUAGCACUGUAGACGCCGACUUUACCAACCAAGAUAGUGUAUGUGUGUGACAUUCAGCUAACAUUGAUCUAGGCACUUAGUUUGCUACCACAUUGUUCCCUUCAUUGAUUGAAACUGUAAAUAACAUAACACUUUAAGGCAGCUAAGCAAAUAUUUUAAUAAGCCAUGAAAGGCAAGAUGCCAGAGAAAAUCUGUAUAUUCAGCUAUUUGGAGAACUCGUGUUUUCCACAAAUUAAACUGGAGAUGUCAUUUGAAAUUUUCUUCCCUUAAACAUGCUGUCACAACAUGGAUUCCUUCUCAUGGAUGUCUUUCUAGGCUUAUAAAUAUAUGGUGUGAUUGCUAUAAUUUUGUGAAAUUUUAUUCAGCAAUUAAUAGUGAUUUCAGCAAUAUGUACUAAGAUUCCAAGGCAGAAAUAAAUGUAUAAAGGAUUUGAGCCUGUAUGUGUAAGAAGAAACUCUCUCUUCAGUCAUAUUUCCUAAAUUCAGUGUAAGUACCUCGCUGAUUUAGCACUGGAGUUAUUCCUUGAAUGUGUAAAUAAUGAUGUUCUAUUCUGACCUAAUGAAUUCCUGUAAUGUGAAUAUUUAAAAUAAAAGAAUUCAAUUUAAAUGUA